AGAGCUCCCAUCGCAGAGCCUGCGGGUUAGGUUGUGAGGCCCGGGCCGGGGGCGGGGAGGAGCCAAGGGGGCGAGCAAGCUCGGUGGCUGGGUGGGUUGGGGCGUUCCGCGCGCCCUUCAUUGAAGCGGCGGUGGCCGGGCUGGGCGCCGGUAGUGGAAAGCGACGGCGCGGCUGGAAAAUGCCAGUCCAUUCCCGAGGGGAUAAGAAGGAGACCAACCAUCACGAUGAGAUGGAGGUGGACUACGCCGAAAAUGAGGGGAGCAGCUCCGAGGACGAGGACACUGAGAGCUCGUCGGUCUCCGAGGAUGGAGAUAGCUCAGUUUGACUUUUAUUUGAUGAAGAUCAAGAUGCAGAUCAUUUUGUGCUUCAGUUAUUUUGAUGAAUGAAUAUAUGUGAUAUGAACAUAGAAAAUGUGGACUAUAGGACAGACCUGGCAAAUCAGCCAUGUGAGCAGUUCUGAAAGAAGAAUCCCAAAAAUGUUUUUGAGCAAUGUUAGCCUUUAAAGGACACAGUCAUUUUGGUGCUACAUUCUGAAAUGGAUGAUGAAGACUGUGAAAGAAGAAGAAUGGAAUGUUUGGAUGAAAUGUCCAAUCUUGAAAAACAGUUUACCGAUCUCAAAGAUCAACUUUAUAAAGAACGAUUAAGUCAGGUGGAUGCAAAACUACAAGAAGUCAUAGCUGGAAAAGCACCAGAAUACUUGGAACCGCUGGCAACUUUACAGGAAAAUAUGCAAAUUCGUACAAAGGUAGCAGGAAUCUAUAGAGAGCUCUGCUUAGAAUCUGUAAAGAACAAAUAUGAAUGUGAAAUUCAAGCUUCUCGCCAGCAUUGUGAGAGCGAAAAGCUGUUGCUAUAUGAUACAGUCCAGAGUGAACUAGAGGAGAAGAUAAGAAGGCUUGAAGAGGAUAGGCACAGCAUUGAUAUUACCUCAGAGCUGUGGAAUGAUGAGCUUCAGUCAAGAAAAAAGAGGAAGGAUCCUUUCAGUCCUGACAAAAAGAAGCCAGUUGUUGUUUCAGGUCCAUAUAUAGUUUAUAUGCUACAAGAUCUUGAUAUUCUUGAAGACUGGACAACAAUUAGGAAGGCAAUGGCUACAUUGGGGCCACACAGAGUGAAAACGGAACUUUUUGAACUGAUCCCUUUAGCACCUGUGAAACUGGAAAAACAUCUGCACAGUGCUAGAUCUGAAGAGGGAAGACUAUAUUAUGAUGGUGAAUGGUAUAUACGUGGACAAACAAUAUGUAUUGAUAAAAAAGAUGAAUGUCCUACAAGUGCUGUAAUUACAACAAUUAACCAUGAUGAAGUUUGGUUUAAGAGGCCUGAUGGAAGCAAAUCUAAGCUUUACAUUUCACAGCUACAGAAAGGAAAAUAUUCAAUUAAACAUUCAUAAUCAUGAUUUAAGUGUUAUCUAAAUUUACCUUAUUAGUGUUACCAAAUGUAAGUGCCAUGAGAGUAAAAAAAUGUAUUCAAUAACUUAAUAUUCUCACUGAAUCAUGAGAGAAUGUGUAUUUGUAGGUAGUACUCUAAAUAGAUCUCAUUGAUAUGUUAUUAAAAGAAACAGUAAUAAAAAUUUUAUCACGAUCCUUACGUUGAUUUGCCUCUUAGGUCCGAUGACCAAUAGGUAUUCUGUAUAUGGUAGGGGUUUCUUUCUAAACAUUUUUCUUUGGUUUUAAAAAAAGUUAUGCAAAUUUGUCUUAUCUUUAGUAAACUAUGACUACAUUUAUCUGCAAUUUUUAAAAUUUUCCAUAUCUUUGUCAUUCAUUGUGUGUUUGUAAAUAAGGCCGAUAGAAUGUUUCCUAUAAAUGGUUUGUACUAGUACAUUAGUGUUAAACCAGAACUGAAAUUUAAACAUAUAUAUAUAUGAGGAUGUAUAUAUGGCAUCAUCAGCUUAUUUAGAACUGAUGGCCAUACCUUACAAUCUUGUUUUACCCAAAAUUAAGCUAUUGGGGUUGAAAGCUAAAAGGAGCACUUUUGUAGAAUAGCAACUUUUCUUUUCCUCUUUCUUGAUUGUAUGGUGGGGUGGUGACCUAUUUUUACAAAUUAUACCUAAUGAGUAAAAUUAGUGUAAAGUGAUAACAUGCUUCUACCUGUAUUUCUAGUGACCCUUUAGCGGCAGGUAUUUAUACCUGGUAUUUAUGAUGCAGUAUAUAAGUGGUGAACAAUAACUGACAGUAUUGUGCUUGCUGUACAUGUCUGGUCUUUUGAAACAGAUUUUAGUAAGCAUUUUCCAGAGGUAAAACUGUGUCCUUAUUCUAAUUUUAUUCCUAGGGCAAAGUAGACAGGGAUUAUUUCCUUGAAUCUAUUUCCAAAUUAAUAUUUUUUUCUUUGGUAUUUCUACACUUUAAGGCCAUUUGGUGCAAUUUAGAAAGUGUUGGCCUCCCUUCCGCUAGCCACAUUCAAAAUUAACUUCCAAAACCUCAGGAACAGUACAAAGAAUUGAAACCCUCAAUAUGGCAGCACAGCCGGCUGUAGUGUAUAUUUAGGGUACACCAAAUCAGGUAUUCCUGGUGGUCUUGUGCACUUUAAUUUCUGUUACAAUGAGUUAAGAGGAUGAGGAAGAAAUCUACUUAUUAACACUUACUGCAGAAAUGUCUGCAUUAUUCCGUUUGUUUUCUUAUUAUUUUACCUCUCCAAACAUCUUCCUGUGCAGAUCACUACUUCAUAGUUGCCAAAUUUUAAAACACUUAACUGCUGAAAUUCAGUGUCAGCAAAGUGAUAUUACGUUGUUCUGUUUCUAAUUAACCUUAGCAAAUGUACAUAAUGUCAAAACCCAAUAGUAUUUGACAGUACUUAUGUAUACAAUGUUUGAUAAGCAUUUUUAAUAAGAUUUGUAUUUUUAAAUUUAGUAUAUAAUAAAAAGAUGUGUUUCAGUGUGA